GCGGCGACUUCCGUGCUCCCGGCGAGCGGGCGGAGAGCGGGGGCCGCACUGGGGAGUGUGGGCUGGGCCGCAGGUGAGCGCGCGGUCCCGGCGAGCAGGUCGGGUCAGCCCAGGCCAGUAACCUCUGAGUUACGGGAGGAGUGAUCGCUAGGGUCCACCCCGGUCCCGGCCAGAUCUGCCAGCUCCCCUCUCUGGCGGGUGUUCUGGUGCCAAGUCUGGGAGCCCAGGUAGCCCUCCGCAGACAGGGCUUCUCGGCACCUCAAUGAGGACGGACGUUGAUGAGGCCAUGAAUGAGGUGGGCUAGGGACAGGGGACCGGGAGACUCACAGAAGGGAGAAGGGUAGCCAUUUGGAUGGACCUUCGCCUUACUUGCGCUCCCAUUCCUGGACUGCGCUCUAGUGACUGUCAGGGCUAAUUCUUCCGCCUUCUCAGGCCUCCUGUGUCCUUGUUAGUAGUUCUUGAAUUUGGGACUACGGCUUCUGGCCUCGUUGGGCCUCCGGGCCCUCGCACUGGGGCAGGUUUCCCAGCAGCCCAGUUGACCUUUACCGGAUGCUUUUGGCAGACGUCCUCCAUGCCGGGCUGGAAAUAUGCGUCACAGUGUUUUUCAGACACUUUUGCCUCUUUCAUUGUGAUACCCUGCCUGGGGACGACUAUGAUGGAGUCUUUAGGUUUUUGUAAUCAGCAAAGGCAUCUGUUAUGCUCCUGCCACCUUUUGGGGGAGAGUGGGUGGAGGAUGUUGUGAUUUUACACUAGGGAGUUUGGGCUGUCAUUCAUUCGUUCAGCAGACCUUUUUUGGGCACUCUGCCAGGCAGGGUAGGAGAGGUGCCUGGAUGGAUAGGGCAUAAUUGGGCCAGACAGACACGGUUCUUAGCCUUUUGGAGCUUAAAGUGUCUUGAGAAACGCAGACAGGGUAAGCCAGCAUCGUGCCUGACACAGAGUAAGUGGUUAUAAGUGUCGAAUAAAGGAAUGAAUUGACUUAUUUGGGAAUGAUUAGAAUGUGAGCAGGACGGUAGCGAGAGACUUUAUGCUGCAUGUGAGAGAUAGUUGUGAACUCAUGCGCGAUAUGUUUUAAGACAGGUUUGGAAAUCUGAACGGACAGUUGCUAUUUAGGGAAGCAUUUACUUAUACAGAGGACUUGCUUUAAAGGUGGAAGUAAAAUGGAGAAGUAUUAGGUUUGGGAUUCUUCAGAGGUGCCUCUUUUAACUAUUACUAUGUCUCUGAAUUUCAUAAAUCCCUGAGUACAAUCUCAGAGUUUGGGAAAAGGAAAGCUCUUCUAGGUAAUGAAAUGCCAGGCUGAUGGGAAAAAACUGUAGGAAGCUCUCCCUAAGUCCAGGGUUUGGACAGAAACCGUAUACCUCUGCAGUGUGUUCUUCCCACUAGAAAGAGUGUAGGCUUUGAAAUUGGAGAGGCCUGGGUUCAAAAUCAGUGGCUCUAUCACUUCUAGUGAUCUUGGAUAAGUUAACAUAAUGUCUGUGAGCCUUUGUGGCCUUCACAAGAGUCUGGGCUAAUAAUUCCUACAUCAUAGAGGUGUUAUGAGGAUCAAAUGAUGAUUAGUGUGUAAAUUGUCAUCAUAGUGCCUGGUGCUGAGACAAUAAGCGGGGGAGUCUUGGAGAUGCUGCAAUUUUUUUUUUUUUUUUAAAUUUCAUGAUGCUGCCUUAUUGCAGGGGUCCUUAACCCCCUGGGCCACAGACCAGUGGUGGUCUUCAGCCCAUUAGAAACUGGGCUGCACAGCAGGAGGUGAGCGGUGGGCAAGCUGGCAAGCAUUACCGCCUGAGCUCCACCUUCUGAUAGAUCAGCAGCGGCAUUAGAUUCUCACAGGAGUGCAAACUCUAUUGUGAACUGCGCAUGUGAGGGAUCUACGUUGUGUGCCCCUUAUGAGAAUCUAAUGCCUGAUGAUCUGAGCUGGAACAGUUUCAUCCCGAAACCAUCCCUCUCCAACCCCCAUCUGUGGAAAAAUUGUCUUCCACGAAACUGGUCCCUGGUGCCAAAUAUAGAUUGGGGACCGCUGCCUUAUAGUGUUACGUCUAGAGAACAUUGGGAUUCCUUCAAAGAGAAUUGGAACCAAAGAGAGAGGGGGAGAAUCAUCUUAUCCUUGGUGAGGUUUCGAUUGUUCACUUUAGAUCAGAGAUAGUAGUGUUGGAGAAAUACCUACAGGGGCAUAAACAGAAAGAUCUUUUAGUGGAUACUUUUGGGCAAGUCUCUUAACCCUCUGAUAGUGGGUUAUGUAUCUACCUCACGUGGUGGACAUGAGGAUUAAGAGAGUGAGUGUAUAUGAAGCACCUAGCCCAAGGCCUGGCAUGUAAGUGCUCAAUAAAUGGUAGCUGUGUUAUUAUAACUGUGAAUGAUCUUUGAUAAUUGAUAAUGGUAAUAAUCAUUUGAGAUGGAAUUGGCCAUUAGAGUGAUCCAAUUUGUGUGUUUUUACAUUACUUUGGUAUUGCCCUACUUCAAUUCAGGAGGCCCUGAGGCCAUUCCACUCCGCUCCCCGCCCCACCCCACCCCACCCCACCCCCCGGGCUUGUACAGUGAUUUUUCACAGAAAAUCUUCAGGUUCUGCGGUAUCCAGAAUGUCAUGUGGCCUGUGUUUUGGACCGUGGUUCGUACCUAUGCUCCUUAUGUCACAUUCCCUGUUGCCUUCGUGGUCGGGGCUGUGGGUUACCACCUGGAAUGGUUCAUCAGGGGAAAGGACCCCCAGCCCGUGGAGGAGGAAAAGAGCAUCUCAGAGCGCCGGGAGGAUCGCAAGCUGGAUGAGCUUCUAGGCAAGGACCACACGCAGGUGGUGAGCCUUAAGGACAAGCUAGAAUUUGCCCCGAAAGCUGUGCUGAACAGAAACCGCCCAGAGAAGAAUUAAUGGAGGACACAGGGCCCUAUGGUCCUACUGUGGGUGGUGACUUGUCCUGCUACCAUGUUGACAGAGCCCCAGAACCCACAUCUAAUUGGCUUUGUUGCUUAUUCUGGCCCUUCCCACACCACACAGCCACACAAAUACUGGCUGCUCCUUGAUGGCCAGGCAGACCCAGCAGCAGCCGAGGGGCCAGUGAAGAGGAAGGCCGCAUCUGUUGUGUGGUGGCCACAAGCACUCAGGCAUCUGAGUUUACUGGUGCACUGCUGGGAGGAGAGUUAUGAGAUGAACAUUGGCUGUCAAUCUCUGUGGGCAGGCGGUUUGGCCUCUAGUGGGAAUGGCUGGGAUUUGGGCGUUGCCUUUAGGAGGGAUACCUGCAUGUCUAGUUCCAGUCUGCACUGGAAAGAAUUCAAAUAUGCACCUGGCUCCCUUCACUAUUUUGCCCUAUCCUUUGUGCUCAUUCUUACUGAAAUCUGUCUUGUCAGCUCAGGAAUGGGAUUCCCCCAGGAAGGAAAGCACUUUUCUGUUCUGGGAAGCCCAGACUGUUCACUUUGGGGCAGGGACGAACAUGUGCCUCGUGAAUUUGCUUGAAAACAGUCACCAUCUUCUACCCCCAUCACUGUAUAGUGAAAAACCUGAUUAAAGUGGUAUCUGAGAACCAUAAUGAUCGAAUCUUAUCAUCCAGGUGGUAUUUGGGGGUCUUCUUAGGAGUUAGGCAAGUACAGGCAUUUUAGAGCAGGAUAACAUUGGUAUUAAAGGGUGCCAAGGAGCCCUGGAAACUGCUUUACUAGUGCGGUUGCACUGAACCCUGGAGGCACAGAUUCCCAGGAACCUUUUUACCAUUAUUACAAUUGGCUGCAGCACCUUCAAGUCUAAAUGGAGGUAGACCUCACAUACACACACAUAGACGCCUUUCCCUAUAAAAGUAUAUACGCACAUUCAAGAAAAUUUGGUAGGGAUUUUAAAAAGGUCACCCAUGUUCCCAGCUCGUUAAUAACAACCGUUAACAUUUUGUUGUCUUUUACUAAUUCUCUGCAUAGGUUUUAGAGAUAGUUAUCAUUACUGUACAUUUAAUUUUAUAUACUUUUCUCACUAUUAUCAUUUUCCCAUUUUACAUGGUCAUCAUAAUUGGUUUUUUGGAGACAGGGUCUCACUCUGUCACACAGGCUGGAGUGCAGUACAAUUACGGCUCAGUGCAACCUUGACCUCCUGGGCUCAAGUGAUCCUCUCACUUCAGCUCCUCAAGUAGAUGGGACUACAGGAGUAUGCCACCAUGCCCAGCUAAUUUUUUUAUUUUUUUGUAGAACCAGGUCUCACUAUGUUGCCCAGGCUAGUCUCAAACUCCUGGGCUCAAGUGAUCCUCCGGCCUUGGCCUGUAGUUUCUUUUUUCUUUUUUUUUGGAGAUGGACUCUCAUUCUGUCACCCGGGCUGGAGUGCAGUGGCGUGAUCUUGGCUGACUGCAACUUCUGCCUCCUGGGUUCAAGCGAUUCUCCUACCUCAGCUUCCUAAGUAGCUGGGAUUACAGGCGUGCGCCAUCGUGCCUGGCUAGUUUUUGUGUUUUUAGUAAAGACAGGGGUUUCACCAUCUUGGCCAGGCUGGUCUCGAACUCCUGACCUCAAGCGAUCCCAUCUGCCUCGGCCUCCCAAAGUGCUGGGAUUACAGGUGUGAGGCACCGUGCCUGGCAGUCUGUAGUUUUUUUUUGUUGUUGUUGUUGUUGUUGUUUUAAAUAUGGAGUCUCGCUGUAUUGCCCAGGCUGGAGUGCAGUGGCGCGAUCUUGGUUCACUGCAACCUCCACCUCUUGGGUUCAAGCGAUUCUCCUGCCUCAGCCUCCUGAGUAGCUGGGAUUACAGGUGUGCGCCGCUACGCCUGGCUAAUUUUUGUAUUUUUAGUAGAGACAGGGUUUCACCAUGUUGGUCAGGCUGGUCUCAAACUUCUGACCUUGUGAUCUGCCUGCCUUGGCCUCCUAAAGUGCUGGGAUUACAGGCGUGAGCCACCGUGCCUGGCUGUAGUUGUUUAUAAUAGCAACAUAAUUGUCUAUCAAGUGGGAGUAUGACAUAAGUUUAUCCUGGACAAUUUCCAUAUUGCUGGACAUUUGAAUUGUUUCUGGUUGGUCACUCGUUUAGAUACUGCAACGAAUAUCUUAUAUGAAGCUUUUCCUGCGUUUUGGAAUAAACAGUAAAAAUAGUAAAUGUCAUUUUGGAUGAAAUGGGAUAAAUGAGCAGUUUUGAGGAUCUCAUGCAUAACACCAAAUGUCUUUCCAAAAGGGCUCUAGGAGUUUCUACUAAAUCUUACCACUGAAGACGUUGCUGGUAAGGCUGUGAGGGGAGUAAAAGCAGAGAGCAGGAAGAAGCAUAAGAAGCUGUUGCCUCUUGAAGCCUACUGAUGUUUAACUAAAGUCAGCACAGGGCAGUAGUGAGCAUUUGAUGAAUUGAUCUGCCUCUAAAAGGGAGUGGGUAUUGGCCCUGCUUCUUAGGUUCUCUCUCGUGAGGCCUGAUGGUGUCCACAGGUGGGUGAGGGUGGAGUUCCUGAACAGUUAGAGGGGCCAGCUGUGAAGAGGUGCCAGCUGGAGGUGCCUUCCAGGACCUGGUGGUGGCCUGAGAGGAGGGAGCAGGUUGAGUCGUUGGCUUCUUCUAAGGCUCCCUGAGGCCUAGUGGGAAUGCGGAAAUGAGCUGCUGUUGCUUCCCAGGGAACAAAUCGGAUGGAACUUGGGAAGAGACUGUCAGCUACCAAGUAAGGAGAUUUCUGGUUCUGGCUGCAGGUUCUGGCUGAUGAGCAGGCCUUAUCGGCACACCAGUGCUGCCACCCUAUGGCAGUCCUGGGCAUUACCAAGCCUGCAGUCACUUCCCUGGGCUAAACCAAACACUAGUGCUGACAGAGGUCAGGUGACAAAUGAGCCACCACGCUGGCAGAAAGUAUAGACCUGCCGAAAGGGGGCAGUGGUGACUCACCUUCCAAUCUGCUGCUCAUCCAGUGGUACCAGAUUUUUGAAUUUUUCUAAAAGAUGUUCUAAGAGCUCCAGAGGGGGUAAAAAAAAAAAAAUGAAGAGAUGCUAGAAAUUCAGGGUUUUUUGGUGUGUGUAACCUUCUGAUUUUCAAGUGUUGAUAAUUCAUUAUACAAAAUUCUAAGCAUGCUAUCAUACCCGUGGGGUUAAUUUGACCCAGUGGCUGCCAAUUUGUGACCUCUCAAACUGCCUCCUCCUUCUGAUGACACCUAUAAUUAUGGUUUUUUUUUUUUUUUUUUUUUUGGCGAUCUAACAACUUGUUACAAAUAUUAGAUCCCAGAAUUGGUUUCCCUCAAAACACUUUUGGGCAUCCUGUACAAAGGCAGCUUAAUAACCUAAGAAAAAUGUGAGGAUGGAAAGCCUACAGAAAUAAUAGCAAACACAUUUCCCAUGGACAUUUUUGGAUUUUCAGAUCUUUUAAAAUAUCCCUGUCACCACCCGUUGGCCUCCACUUGGUGUCUGGUCGAGAGAGCCCUAUCUUUGGGAAUCCAGGUGGCUCCCUUCUUCCAGUCUCACUUUGAUUGUGCCCCCUUUUAAAUUCUUUUCUUUCCUUUCCAAGGGCACUUUGUCACUGAAUUCUUCCUCUAGCAAGUCUAUUAGUGUUCUCAGCUAGAUCUUUCUUUCCCACAGGCUGGCUGAAAUCAGCCGUUGCGGUGGCUGUAAGAUAGUAUAUGUGCUCUUGCCUCUGCUCGGGUGACAUUAGAUAGCAAGGUUUAUGUGGACGUGGGUAUAGACAGGUCAGGGUUGCUGGGAUGAACCAAGGUGCAGACCGGUUUUCUUCCAUGCUUGCUGAUUCACCUUGGAGGCAUGUGACCCUCUUUUUGACUGGCCUUCCAGUCACAGUUCACUGAAACACAUGAGUGAGUGGAUGUGCUUGGGGCUUUUUGCUCCCCGCUUACCCCCGUCUCUUCCCAGCCCAAUGAUGGUGGUGGCUUUAGUAUAGGGUCCUCUCCGAGCACGGCAGGAAUCACUUCUCUCCCUGCAGCGGUUCAGUGUCUGGUGCUUUUCCACUCUUUCUAGACUCUUUCCUGUGCCUGUUGCUGUGUUAGCACAAGUCGGCUGGGCAGCUGCCAGAACAAGCCUGCCAGGGAGCCUUUUGACUCUGGUCAGCUCCCCAGGGCUCCAGGCUGGUGGGACUGCCGCUGAGUGAAACAUCAUGGAAUUAGCCUUGCCAGAGUCUGGGUUGGGAGCCAGGCAGUGAAAAUGUAAAAGCCCCUCCGUCUUGCUCACUUUUCCUUUUCUACUUUGCUUUAGAUCUCUAAGCACUUGUAGGGUAGGGAGCCAGGGCAGUGUAGCAGAGGAAAAAUAAAGUGGAUUCUAGAGUCUGACAGGCUCGAGUUAUGAAUACUGCCUUAACAAUUAACUGGAUGACCUUGGGCAAGUCACUUAGCCCUUCUGAACCUCAAUAUCCUCACCUGUAAAAUAGGGGUAAGAAUUUUUGUUGGGUUGUUGUGAGGAUGAGGUAAUUAUGUAAGGUUCUUAGCAUAGUACGCUAAGAACUUUAUAUACAUUGUCACAGACUGUGCUAAAACUUUACAUACAUUACCUCAUCCUCACAACAACCAGUAGGUACUCAGUAAAUGUUAGCAGCUUUAAUUGUAUUGCAGGAAGAACCUAUGUUUCCUGCAAUAGUUGUGUGUAUCCUUGUGACCCUGGUGAGGUGGGGAUCUAGGGGAGAGAGCAGCCUUGGCUGAGGGACAACAGGGACCCUCAUAGACCUGGUGGUUGAGGGCUGCUUAGAAAUAUUUCACAGAGAGAACUGGCUUGCAUAAGAACCAAGAAGCACAAGCUGGUCAGGAGAUUGCAGGCUCCACACCUGCCUUAGUGGUAGUUCCAUCAGUGCAGUCUGCAAAGUCAGAGGGAAGCAGAUUGGCCAGAAUGCCCAGGAGGUCACAGAUCAGGAGAAUUGGGAGGGGAAAGAGCCUUGGACUUGGAGGCAAGCGAUCUGAGUGAUGACCUGGGGUAUGCCGCUUCACCUCUACUGGCCUUGGUUUCCCUGCAAAAUGGGGAACGUGUUCCCUGCUGAUCGUGUGAAAAGAGUGAGACAACCAGUUUAGAGUGCUCUGAAAACAUGCAAGUGCUAGAUAUUACAGCCCAGUAAAACCUCCUUUAUCUAGUUGGGAUGGCAGCCAGUCUGAAUAAUAAAAUACAAAUACAUGUGCUAUUAUUUCUUUCCUGUACAGAGCGUAUUUUAUAGUAUUUGCUAAGUAGAAGUCUUUAGGGGAAUCAGUUUGAAGAGUGAAGAGUAAUUAGUAACCGGUGUAUCAGUUUUCAUCCUGUUCCAGCAGUGCCUCUGGUACUUAAAAAACAGUUUAUUCUUUUUGAAUUAAACUUGUUAACAUCAA